AGAGCCAGAGCAGGAUGGAGAGGAGACGCAUCACCUCCGCUGCUCGCCGCUCCUACGUCUCCUCAGGGGAGAUGAUGGUGGGGGGCCUGGCUCCUGGCCGCCGUCUGGGUCCUGGCACCCGCCUCUCCCUGGCUCGAAUGCCCCCUCCACUCCCGACCCGGGUGGAUUUCUCCCUGGCUGGGGCACUCAAUGCUGGCUUCAAGGAGACCCGGGCCAGUGAGCGGGCAGAGAUGAUGGAGCUCAAUGACCGCUUUGCCAGCUACAUCGAGAAGGUUCGCUUCCUGGAACAGCAAAACAAGGCGCUGGCUGCUGAGCUGAACCAGCUGCGGGCCAAGGAGCCCACCAAGCUGGCAGACGUCUACCAGGCUGAGCUGCGAGAGCUGCGGCUGCGGCUCGAUCAACUCACCGCCAACAGCGCCCGGCUGGAGGUUGAGAGGGACAAUCUGGCACAGGACCUGGCCACUGUGAGGCAGAAGCUCCAGGAUGAAACCAACCUGAGGCUGGAAGCCGAGAACAACCUGGCUGCCUAUAGACAGGAAGCAGAUGAAGCCACCCUGGCCCGUCUGGAUCUGGAGAGGAAGAUUGAGUCGCUGGAGGAGGAGAUCCGGUUCUUGAGGAAGAUCCACGAGGAGGAGGUUCGGGAACUCCAGGAGCAGCUGGCCCGACAGCAGGUCCAUGUGGAGCUUGACGUGGCCAAGCCAGACCUCACCGCAGCCCUGAAAGAGAUCCGCACGCAGUAUGAGGCAAUGGCGUCCAGCAACAUGCAUGAAGCCGAAGAGUGGUACCGCUCCAAGUUUGCAGACCUGACAGACGCUGCUGCCCGCAACGCGGAGCUGCUCCGCCAGGCCAAGCACGAAGCCAACGACUACCGGCGCCAGUUGCAGUCCUUGACCUGCGACCUGGAGUCUCUGCGCGGCACGAACGAGUCCCUGGAGAGGCAGAUGCGCGAGCAGGAGGAGCGGCACGUGCGGGAGGCGGCCAGUUAUCAGGAGGCGCUGGCGCGGCUGGAGGAAGAGGGGCAGAGCCUCAAGGACGAGAUGGCCCGCCACUUGCAGGAGUACCAGGACCUGCUCAAUGUCAAGCUGGCCCUGGACAUCGAGAUCGCCACCUACAGGAAGCUGCUAGAGGGCGAGGAGAACCGGAUCACCAUUCCCGUGCAGACCUUCUCCAACCUGCAGAUUCGAGAAACCAGCCUGGACACCAAGUCUGUGUCAGAAGGCCACCUCAAGAGGAACAUCGUGGUGAAGACCGUGGAGAUGCGGGAUGGAGAGGUCAUUAAGGAGUCCAAGCAGGAGCACAAGGAUGUGAUGUGAGGCAGGACCCACCUGGUGGCCUCUGCCCCGUCUCAUGAGGGGCCCGAGCAGAAGCAGGAUAGUUGCUCCGCCUCUGCUGGCACAUUUCCCCAGACCUGAGCUCCCCACCACCCCAGCUGCUCCCCUCCCUCCUCUGUCCCUAGGUCAGCUUGCUGCCCUAGGCUCCGUCAGUAUCAGGCCUGCCAGACGGCACCCACCCAGCACCCAGCAACUCCAACUAACAAGAAACUCACCCCCAAGGGGCAGUCUGGAGGGGCAUGGCCAGCAGCUUGCGUUAGAAUGAGGAGGAAGGAGAGAAGGGGAGGAGGGCGGGGGGCACCUACUACAUCGCCCUCCACAUCCCUGAUUCCUGUUGUUAUGGAAACUGUUGCCAGAGAUGGAGGUUCUCUCGGAGUAUCUGGGAACUGUGCCUUUGAGUUUCCUCAGGCUGCUGGAGGAAAACUGAGACUCAGACAGGAAAGGGAAGGCCCCACAGACAAGGUAGCCCUGGCCAGAGGCUUGUUUUGUCUUUUGGUUUUUAUGAGGUGGGAUAUCCCUAUGCUGCCUAGGCUGACCUUGAACUCCUGGGCUCAAGCAGUCUACCCACCUCAGCCUCCUGUGUAGCUGGGAUUAUAGAUUGGAGCCACCAUGCCCAGCUCAGAGGGUUGUUCUCCUAGACUGACCCUGAUCAGUCUAAGAUGGGUGGGGACGUCCUGCCACCUGGGGCAGUCACCUGCCCAGAUCCCAGAAGGACCUCCUGAGCGAUGACUCAAGUGUCUCAGUCCACCUGAGCUGCCAUCCAGGGAUGCCAUCUGUGGGCACGCUGUGGGCAGGUGGGAGCUUGAUUCUCAGCACUUGGGGGAUCUGUUGUGUACGUGGAGAGGGAUGAGGUGCUGGGAGGGAUAGAGGGGGGCUGCCUGGCCCCCAGCUGUGGGUACAGAGAGGUCAAGCCCAGGAGGACUGCCCCGUGCAGACUGGAGGGGACGCUGGUAGAGAUGGAGGAGGAGGCAAUUGGGAUGGCGCUAGGCAUACAAGUAGGGGUUGUGGGUGACCAGUUGCACUUGGCCUCUGGAUUGUGGGAAUUAAGGAAGUGACUCAUCCUCUUGAAGAUGCUGAAACAGGAGAGAAAGGGGAUGUAUCCAUGGGGGCAGGGCAUGACUUUGUCCCAUUUCUAAAGGCCUCUUCCUUGCUGUGUCAUACCAGGCCGCCCCAGCCUCUGAGCCCCUGGGACUGCUGCUUCUUAACCCCAGUAAGCCACUGCCACACGUCUGACCCUCUCCACCCCAUAGUGACCGGCUGCUUUUCCCUAAGCCAAGGGCCUCUUGCGGUCCCUUCUUACUCACACACAAAAUGUACCCAGUAUUCUAGGUAGUGCCCUAUUUUACAAUUGUAAAACUGAGGCACGAGCAAAGUGAAGACACUGGCUCAUAUUCCUGCAGCCUGGAGGCCGGGUGCUCAGGGCUGACACGUCCACCCCAGUGCACCCACUCUGCUUUGACUGAGCAGACUGGUGAGCAGACUGGUGGGAUCUGUGCCCAGAGAUGGGACUGGGAGGGCCCACUUCAGGGUUCUCCUCUCCCCUCUAAGGCCGAAGAAGGGUCCUUCCCUCUCCCCAAGACUUGGUGUCCUUUCCCUCCACUCCUUCCUGCCACCUGCUGCUGCUGCUGCUGCUAAUCUUCAGGGCACUGCUGCUGCCUUUAGUCGCUGAGGAAAAAUAAAGACAAAUGCUGCGCCCUUCCCCAGAGUGGACUCUGAUCUGUUCAUGAGAGGGCGGGACUGGGGCCAAGAUGUAGCCUUUGACAAGACCAACUCAUUUCUUAUUACUGAUCAUCUCUGGGGCCCAUGCCCUCACCAAAUUCCACCCGCAGCCAAAGAGGACAUACACCAGCUCCCUCCACUCUUUUCUUCCUUCCUCUCCCUGCUACCUGCAACUCAACCAGCACAAUCUUCAUAGGCAAGAAAGCAAAGCAGCUCAAACAUGAUUCAACACUGAUCAGUGUUUACCACUGGAUAAAUCUGAGUUCACACUUUCCUUCUCUGACCUAAAUGUGAAGUCAGGAAACACAUGUGCCCUACUUCCAUCCUGAGCUCAGUCCCCAAUCUCCCACCAGCCUCAGGCCCCUCCACUUCUCAGAUCAGGUCCCAGACCUGCCCAUGAAAAUGGGGAGCAGGCUGUAACAGAUUUGUCCACAUGUUCCUACCACCUGUCCCAACCCAGGGUACCCACCCAGAGACAUCUGGUAUCAUUUAACAAACACAUUGAAGGACAACUGGUCUUCAGAGCUGAAGAGAGCUCCUAGGGGGAGAAGCUGGGACAACAGUGAAAUAAGUAGCAGCAGCAACGACAGAAGUGAAUGGUGACAAAGACUGCUGUGAUGAGCAGGUAGCCUAUCAGGGUGAGCUCCACAGCCGAGCGAGUCUCAGGAUCUGAGAACGAGGCUGGGUAGUGCCCAUGAGAUGUCACACCCAGCCGGAAGCCAGCAACUAGCACACCCUGCCUCCAGCAAUAGUAGAUGCCCCGGUCAUCCAGCUGGGUGAAGCGGAUGUGGAGCUGGUUGCCGUGGUCAAUGAACACCCUCAUGGACCUGUUGACACCCUUCAGGUACUGUGUGCGGUAGAGGUGCUGGCGGUCUUUGUCCCAGGCCACUGCAUGCUCUGGCCGGGCCCCAGGACAGGAGAUGAUGAGUCCAUGGCCCAGUCUCUGCUGGUGGAACUGAAUGGGCACCUGGGGCACCCAGGGCCGGCUGCCCACUUUGGACACAUAGUUAAUGAUGGCCAGCACGCCCUCCCGGAUGGUCUUUGUCUUCUCACAGGGUACUAAGCAGCUCCGAACCAGCACCUCAGGCGUGUGGUCCCUGGCCUUGGUCCGCAGCUUCCUUGGCACAGCCCUUGAGCCACAAGACACCACAUCGGGCACGGCCUUGAGGUAGCGUGGGGAGAGGUCUGGGCUCUGCAGGUAGCAGAGGCCGAUGCGCCACUGCUCCCCACGCACUCCGCAGCGGUCACAGGGGGUCCAUUCCCAGAAGGUGGUGAAGACAUGGAGGUGCCCAUAGUAUUCAUCUGCAAAGGGCUCCUGGCCCUUGUCCUGGAAAGUGGCCACCAUUCCCUCACUGUUCUGGAUGUCCACAUCGUAGGCGUAAAAGUAGUCCCCCUUGCGGGUGCCGCAGAAGUACAGGCCUGAGUCCUCAGACUGAGCCCUGAAAACCAACAAGCUGAACAUGCGGAUGCUGAAGCGGGUCAGCAUGUCGCUGCCCACACGUACCUGGGCUGCCUCCGUCAGCACCCGCCCAUCAAAGUCCGUCAGCACUUUGGUGUGGCUGCUACCUAGGUGCUUUUGGUAGAACCAGACUACAGCUGGCACCUCUUCGGGUUUGCAGUGACAGGGAAGCUCAAAGCUCAUGUCGGCCAGGUAGGCUGCAUUUUCAAACAUCAGGAAAGCAGGGCAGGGGGUCCUCUGAAAAAUGUUUUCCUUCUCCACAAUUUCAAAGGCCUGGAGCCCCCAUGCCCACAGGAGCACAGUGGUGAGGGCCAGGUGCAUACCUGAAGGAGGCAGGGGUCAGAGGGGCAGGGCAAAACCAGGGCAUUAAAGGCUCAUAGGGCUCCUAGAAAGCUCUGCUAAGCGGAAGCCUCUAGAUGAGGAAAGGAUUAUGCAGCCAGGAAAAGCAGCAACAAUCUGCAGAGGAAGCCGCCAAGUGCAAGGCAAUUUAUUCCCAGUGGAUGUACAAGAUGCCCUUCUAACAUUCCAGACCUGAUCUCAGGGUGGGGGGGGAAAGCCAUUCUAGAACCUGGCCUUUACUCCCCUUUCUAGAACACUGGCGCUCACCCAAGAAUGGGUCAAAGGAAACCGGAAUGAGAAGGGCGGGCCGAGGUGCUCGGGCAGGGAGAUCUCUGCCUCAGUGCUCCAGGCCCUGCCCUGCCAGCCUGGUGGAAAAGUCUUUCAUCAACCUGGGGGAUGAAGGAAACCCACCCUCCUGCAUAUCUGGCCAUCCGGGAGGCUGGCUGGACCUGAGCUGAUGGCUUGGGACUUUCCCAGGCCCAACCUGCACAAGAACUGAGUCUCUAGGGGAAAAUUCAACACCUCAAAUGAUGUAGUAUUUGAUCAUUUGUUGAUUACAUGUCCAUUCAUUGGUUUGGGGCUAUAAACAUUCUUGUUAAGAGCUGUGGAGAUCAGUGUUUGUUUACCAUAAAGAUUUUGCUUUUUCCCUUUUA